UGCAUUGGCCAGAUAUGUCGUCACUCACAAAACUUCGAGCUCAUUGGUGCAAAAGCUCCAGGAGGCGGUGGGUGAUUGGUUGGUUGCUGUUCCUGCCCCCACGCCUGUCGUGGUUUAGCUGAACUGAGCUGAAAUCCUAAAGGCCGCGGAGUCGGCGGUGUUGUAGGUAGCGGUACCUUGAGUGGCAACAGAAUUCGAUUAAAUUACAAUGGGAAACAUUUUUGAAAAGCUCUUUAAAAGUCUACUUGGGAAAAAAAAGAUGCGGAUUCUUAUAUUGAGUUUGGAUACAGCUGGAAAAACCACCAUCUUGUAUAAAUUGAAGCUGGGGGAGACUGUGCCUGCCGUCCCUACAGUAGGUUUCUGUGUGGAGACAGUAGAAUAUAAAAAUAACACCUUCGGUGUCUGGGAUGUUGGCAGCCACUUCAAAAUCAGACCUCUGUGGCAGCAUUUUUUCCAGAACACAAAAGGUGCCAGAAGCCCAGGAAGCACACAUCAAGGCUCACUUGCCAGCGGGGUGCUGCCAAUAAAAUGUAGUCACGUGGAAUUUGGAAUGUGGAAAGGAGGUAGAAGUCAUCCUUUCCUCCCCCAUAGCAGCAGGUGUGCAGGCUCUGGUGGUCAGCUGGACUCCAUACUCCCCCACCAGUCACCAGCCUGGGGACCGUGGGGCUGCAAGGACCUCAGCAGCGGUUUCCCAAGUUUCCUGACUUCUUCCAUCCUCUGGAAAUCAGCUGUGCUGCUCACUCCCAAAGCCUGACAAGUUGAUGCCACUGCUGUCUGAGGGCUCCUCUGGCUCAACAAUCAGCUCAGUGCUUGUGUAGUUCUUCCGGGCUUGUAACACCUUCAUGAACGCUCCUUCUGGAUUCCCUACCGAUGCUUCUUCAGCUGUCAAAAAAGAAGAGACUGCUUUGAUCAUGAAAGAUGAUGGGAUGGGAUGCAUCAGUCCAUAGCUGUACACCCCAGUCACACAGAGUAGGAGUCAGCAAACAUUCGAGUGCCAUUCAGAGAGGAGAAACACACACCCAAUCCUAAACCUAUGAAAUGGCAACAACAAAAGGAGAAAAUACAUCUUUUGAAAACACGGCCACCUACUUGGAACAUUCCAUAGUGUGACAUAGAGUAACUCUGUUUAGGAUUAUUUCGUUGAUCCCCAGAGGCCAAUUGCCCAGUGCUCAGUCAAAGCCCAAGGUGGAAGACAAGUGCUUCCCUGAUGAGCUGGCCUCUCUGCAGACUGCUCCGUACCCUGUGCUGUCCUGCCUCAGAUGCAGAGAGAGCACAAGGCUCCUGCUCUCCUCGUCCUCGGUGCACCUGUGUUCGUGCUACCAUCACAGCUGAAUGCAAUGAAAGGCGGUCCUCUGAGAGGAGCAGGGUGGAGAUGCUAAAGUGGAGGCCCCGUCCCAUUGCUGAUAGAUCCUCAUCUGGCAUGCGCUCCACCCUCCCCAUUCUCUGCUCCCACGUAUCGUAGCCCCAUCACAGAAGAUGUGACAUGGAAAAACGCACUGUGUCCACCCUAGUUCUUAAAUUUGGGCAGGGAUUUGGGGUGUAUGUUAAGAGUUUUUCAAAUUUGCCAGAUUGCAUGCCUAUGUUGUUAAAUACACAAUGAAUCCCUGGUAUGAUAGCAGUUUCUGGAUAAACAUUACUUGAGGUCCUAAAAUGCAGAAGGGAAAAAGCAACUUUUGUCAGAUGCCUACUUUGCUUUCAUUUCAUCUCUAAUAUUUUGGAUGGGGAAUCAUCCAAAGCUUCUGACUGCAUGAAGGUCAGGUGUGCCAGUGUGCAGCUGGGUUUCUUUUCUAGAAUUAAAAGUACUUUGGGUGGUGGUGAGGGUCAGAGGAAGAAGUAAAGAUUGUGAGAAAGGGGAAGAAACAUGGGCUUGGGGAGAACCCAGAAUUGGGGCCAGAAGACCUGGCACUAGGCUACAGCACUUAGCACCUCUGAUCUUGUUUUUCCUCAUCUGUAAAAGGAGGUUAACAAAGCUUUUCUGCCCACUUCUUGGGGAGAAGGGAAUAACAUAAUUGGUAAAAAAAAAAAAAAAAAGUUUUGAAAAAUAAGCAACACUGACUUUAUGUAACCAAGCAUUAUUAAUUCUCCACCCCAUAUCACUGGUAGAUACCUGUAUUCAAGCUAUCUGGACAUGAAAGCAGUCACAUUUUAGAAGUCAUGAAGUUGAUGCUAAUAAGCCUAAUCUACAGAAACACUCUUGAAAGCCCUUGAGCGUUUGUUCUGUGAAUAGAAAGGUUUGAGAUUCGGAGCAAGUUCAGAGUUGGAUGGUCUAAGAAUGGAAAAGCCCUCCAUUCCAUUAGAAGAGCCAGGUAGCAAUUUCUGGUUAUGGAACCAGAAGCUCUCAGGCUUCAAAUAAAACAGCAUCACUUGUACUCUUAUAAAACUGUAAAAACAGAAAGACCAAAACCGUAUCUACAUCUGUCCUAUAAGGCAGAGAGUACUUGAGAUCUCAUGGAUUUAAAACCAGCUUACAAACUACAUUGCACUAUAUGAAGAAAUUAUCACUGUGGGCAAAGCAUCAAGCAGAGAGCACAGUAUACAGUGUGUGGAUGUUAAUGUUAUUCCCUAGCCUUCCCAUUCCUUUGUCUUGGUCCUUUCUGCAUAUGGAACAGUUCUAUUAUUAAAUUUUGUAAUAGUAACUGAGAACCUGACUUUCAGCAAGGGAGUAGUUCGGAAAUUGAGGGAGUUUAACUCUGAAUGAGUAAAUAAAAAUAAAGCAAUUAUGUCAUUAGCUUAAAAUUUUAUCAUCAUUAAAAAUAAAAAGUUUGAAAACAAAUACUUAAUGUAACAAUUUAUCACCGCGCAAUUUGGACUCACGACAAUGUAUGGUGUUUGUCAGACAUGCACUGUUGCAAUGCAGCUUGACUGUCUUGCAGACAGCCUCAAUGCUGUUUUUAAAUUGGCAGAGGCAGCAGGCCAUAUGGCUAGGUAAGAUCCUAUAGAUGAAAACAGAGAGCAAUAAAUUAGCGGUAAAGCGGUUACUUGAGUAGGUAAAGGAGGCAGCCAACGCUACCACAGGUGUGGGAAAAAGGUGUCAUUGAAGCCUAUGGACUGGACAGUUGGGUAGGAACCAGAAGGCCAAUAGGAAGGAGGACAAAAGUGCCCAACUGAAGGGUAAGCAUGGCAGUGAGUAUGGUAUGCCUAGAAUAAAGAUGGUUGGGAUUAGAAUUGGGUGACAGUGAUUAGUAGUUUCAGAAGUAUCUCUUCCCAAUUCAAAAGUCUCACUUUGGGCUGAAAGUACAGAGGAAGAAGGUAGACUUUUAAGAAGUCUGAAUAAGCCCCCAACUUCUGGAGUCCCUUUCUCAAUUCCUGUUGGGAGUGGGAAAUAUUAUAAAUUACUCUGGGCAUUAAAAAUAGCUUAGUUUAACCUGGAUUGCGGAGUUAAAAAAUAACAAAGACUGCAUUGGUCAAAUCUGGACAAUUUGAGCAUUCAAAAGAAUAACAACAAUAAGUUACAACAUAUUUAAUAUAAAGAAGAAUCCACGAAGAGUGAUAUUGAAAAAGAAAGAGGAGGAGUUCUUCUUCAAUGAAAUAAUGCCAGCUAGUAAAUGUAGAAGGAAUGACAGAAUUUUUAAAAGUGUCACUUUGCAACCGUCAGUGUAAUACAAAUUCAUUCAGACAAGGAUUAUCAUUGAUGCACAUUUGGGUGAAAAAACAUUUGAGAACAGGAUCUUCACUGAACUCAAAGUAACAACCCACAGAUUAUUUAUUAAUUACCAAGGGGAAAAUUAUUAUUUUUUAUUUUUAUUUUUAUUUUGUCACCCAGGCUGAAAUACAGUGGCAAAAUUAUACCUCAAUGCAGCCUCAACCCCCCUGGGCUCAAGGGAUCCUCCAAAUUCAGCCUCCUGAGUAGCUGGGAGUAUAGGCUUGCACCACCAUGCCCAGCUAAUUUUUUUUUUUUUUUUGUACUUUUGUAUUUUCAGUAGUGACAGAGUUUCCCCAUGUUGCUCAGGCUGGUGUAGAACUCCUGGGCUCAAGCAAUCCUCCCACCUCGGCCUUCCAAAGUGCUGGGAUUACAAGUGGGAGCCACUGUAGCCAGCAAAAUAAUUACAAUGGAGAGACCUGGAAGAUCACCUUAGUCAAGUGAUCAAACUUAGUAUUACAGGCCAUCUGCGGUUACGAGGCAGGAAGGAUACAUCACCUAUGCAGUAUUUUUCCCAAAAAUGCUUAACUUGAAUUUCAUCAUGAGGAAACAGACAAAUCUGGAUUGUGGGACAAUUUACAAGACAACUAUCUUUGACUCUUAAAAAAUGCCAGUGUCAUGAAAGAUCAAAGAAAGUAGAGGCAUGUUUUAGAUUAAAGGAAAUGAAGACAUGACAUGCAGUGCCUGAUCUUUGAUUGGAUUCUGUACUAUUCUUUCAUCUUUCUGGCUUGUUUGAAUUUUUUCCAAUACGUAAAUUUGGGCAAAAGAGGUGACCGAGACAAUUGAUUAAUUUAUUGUUGUGGCUUAUUGGGGGCACUUUCAGAGAGAUAAAAACAAUCCCUGUAACUGAAGUAAAAGGUUAAUCUUAGGCAGUAUAGCAUGGUCAUUAAGAAUACAGAUUCCAUAGCCAGACUAUGCUUCAAUCUCAGCUCUGAUAAUAAUGUGAAUUUGGGCAAAUUGUUUAAUCUCUGUUCCUUGGCCUUGUCAUUAUAAUAGUACCUACCUCUAAUGAAUUUUGAGGAUCAAAUGAAUCAAUACCUGAAAAAUGCCUGGUGCACAGUCAGUGCUCAAUAAGAGUUAACUAUAAUUAUUGUGUUGCAGAGGUUGUGGGGGGCCUUUUCUGAGUCCUCCAGAAGGAUGGCUUUAUUGGGGCCAUAUUAAGACUAUGAAAACAGAAGAGGGUUUCAUGGAUACAAGAAGUCUGUGAGUUGGGGGUACAAUGUAUAGAGUUUUAGAUUAAAACUGCAUCCAAUAAGUUGGCCUGAGACAUCUUUCAAACCUAUAAAGGAACAAUCACAAGUGACUAGUAGUAUUCCUUUGGGUCCAGUGGAAGCCUCUGAUCUUCAUAUGGAAUGGACCCGGAACCGUAACCCAGCAUUUUGUUGUAUAGCAACCUUACCUCUGCCACAAAGGUGUUUCUUUUGUUUAUUUUGAGGCCGGGUCUCGCUCUGUUACACAGGCUGAGUGCAGUGGUGCAAUCUUGGCUCACUGCAGCCUCUGUCUCCUGUGCUCAAGUGAUCCUCCCACCUCAGCCUCCUGAGUACCUAGAACUACAGGUGUGUGCCACCACACCUGGCUAAUUUUUGUAUAUUUUGUAGAAAUGGGGUUUCACCAUGUUGUCCAGGCUGGUCUCGAACUCCUGGGCACAAGCAACCCUCUCUCUUUGGCCUCCCAAAGUGCUGGGAUUACAGGCAUGAGCCCAAAAUUUUUGGUAUUCUUUUUCUGCCCCCAAGUUUUUAUUUUAAACAUUUUCUUUUUUUCCUUUAAGCCUUAGGAUGGCUGGGAAACAUUUUCAAAUGGUAUAAUGAACACCUGUAUAACUUUCAUCUGGAAUCAGUAGUUGCUAAUACUUUGCCACAUUAGCUUUCCGUGUGUGUAUGUCUAUACAUUUUCUGGACAAAACCAUUUGAGAGUCAGUUGCAGACAUAAUGACCCUUCACCAUUGAAGACUUCAGUGUGCAGCCCCUAAGAACCAAGGCAUUCUCUGACAUAACCAGAGGACUAUCAUCACUCAAUGGAACUUCAUAUUAUCAUUGUCUACUAUGCGGUCCGUAUACACAUUUUCACAAUUGUCCCAAUCAUAACAUGGCUUAAAAAAUUCACAAUCCAAUCAAACAUCAGACAUUACACUUAGUACAUGAUUCUUUAGUCUCCUUCAAUCUAGAACUGUUCCCAGGAUUGUUUUAAAGUAUACUGACAAAUCUUUGAGACU